UGUUUACCUUUUUAAUGGAUAUUAUAUAAUAUGUUUAUAUAAUAUUAAGCUUUUUAUAUGCUUAUUUUUUUCCAGAAUUGUUUUGAACCGAAACUUUGCUUUAGCCGGUAAAAUAAUGUUAAUGCUGGAGGCUUUGUAGCAGUGUAGAAAGGACCCGGGUCUGAAAGUCAAAGACCUACUUAUCACGUUCUUAACUCACCUGGGCCUUUAUUUCCCCAAAGUCCUUGGGCCUCGUAGGCAUCAUCUGUGGAAAGGACAGGGUUCUAGGCUGGAGUGGAAAAGGAAUCUCCUCAGGAGCUCUUACUGCAAGUGUUCCUCCUCCAUUUCAUUUGAGAAUCAUUGUAAUGAUCUGUGGAGCCUUAGUUACUGGUUAUGGACGAGACUGAUUUGUGAGAGUGGAAAAACUCUGGAAGACCAUUGUCCCCACGGGGAAGAUCAGAGAGCCCGACCCGACAUUGAUUAGCUUGUGAGCUGUGCACAACAGCCUGACUUCUCUAAGUGUGCUUCCCCAUCAGCAAAAAGGGGGUAUUGAGAGCUCAGCAUCUUUUACCACAAAGAUUGGAAGAUGUAAAAAAAAUACCCAGCAUAGUACCUGGCUCAUAGUAGACCAGAACAGAUAAUCUGUUUUCUUCUUUUUCUUCUCUACCAAAACUCAGAAUAGUAAGGUGAAGAUGUUAAGCUUACAUGAAGCUUAAUGCUUUAUUGGUCUUGAGGUUAAAAGCGAGUUUGGCUUUUACGGUUUUCUUUCUUUGUACAAUUAUGCCGGUGUGUCUCCACUCUGUAUAUAGUCACUCUUCACAGCAUUUUUAUUGAGUUCUUAGCAUAGAUGUCGAGGUUACAUUUCUGACAUGCAUCACUUUUCUACAUACAUUUCAUGCUGGAAAAGUUCUAAAAUGCUAAAAUGGACAAUAAUUUGUGAGACUUCAUUGAACUAUGGUGACUGUUCCGUGGUGUAUAAAAUAUAUAAUUAAUAAAAUAAUUUAACCAUAGCAGUUGAGUUAAAAAUUAGUGGUCGAUAUACACAUUUAUAUGGUUUGUUUUUUUAAAAGACUGAAGCCAUGAAAGGUUCUUUUUUAAAGUAGUAAAUGAGCGUAUACUUGAUAUUUAGUAACACAUACAGUCUUUUUAAAAAUAAGACAAUCAGUUUUGAUAGAAAUUCCUCCCAGUAUAAAUUGGAAUAAUUAUUAUGAUGAUCACAUUAUAAAAGGAUUUAAAAUGCUUGUUUUGCAAGAUUACAUGGAGUAAAACAAUUAUAAAAAUUCAGCUCCUGUCAUUGUUAUAUGCUAUAUUCUGUAACUUACUUGCCUUCCAGGAUAACAGUGAAUUAGUGUUACAUAUUUUAUUAAUCACAAGUUAAUCAAAUGGGAAGGUAGUUUUAGAAAUUUAGUUAUUUGCUUUAAGGCAUUUCUAGUACAUCCUUUUUUCUUUUGGGAGAAGUUUUAAGAAGGCCUUAUUAUUAACAAGCCUUUUUAAAGGCAUUUGUAGCGUGGUGCAUUAAUACUAACAAAACCUAACCACAAUAAACUAUUUUCUUUUAUCACUCCUGGGAGCUUCAUGAUAUCAUGGCAUUUUAGUUCAUUUUCAGAAGACCCAAAUACAAUCUAAUAGAACAUUACCAAAUAUACAUCUUUAUUUGGAACGGGAUAAAGCGAAUAGAAACAUGGAAAUUUAGAUAAAGUCAGGUGAAACACAUGACAUAAAAUUACUAAUAUUGCUGGAUGUGGUGGCUCAUGCCUGUAAUCUCAGCACUUUGGGAGGCCAAGGUAGGAGGAUCGCUAGAGGCCAGGAGUUCAAGACCAGCCUGGGCAACAUAGUAAGAACUUGUCUCUACAAAAAAUUUAAAAAAUUAGCCAGACAUGGUGGCACAUGUCUGUGGUCCCAGCUACACCAGAGGCUGAGAGGUUGGAAAAUCACUUGACCCUGAGAAGUCAAGGCUGCAGUGAGCCAUGAUUAUGCCACUGCACUCCAGCCUGGGUGAUGAGUGAGACCCUGUCUCAAGUAAAGAAAGAAAAUAACUAAUACUAUGUAGGGCUUUUCACAUCUACAUUAUGAGCUACAUUACUUUUUAGUUAUUCUUUGAUCAACAGUGUGCGUCAAGUUCAUGUUCUAGCCAUCUUUAUGUGGACGGCUUUUAAAGACAUGUCAUGUUCUUAGUGGCUGUUGGCACAAUGUGGUAAAACAUUAAAAUGAUAGAUAAGCUAAUGACUGUAUUCCUUCUGGAGUGGUCCCUUCCUUGGGCAUUGGUUAGCACACGUAUGAGGUAUACUAAGUAACAGUGGUGAUUUGCCAGUGAUCCCAAGGGUCUCUCUUCGGGGACAGUUGUUUGAAGUUCCACCUUGUUAUAUUGUACAGGCAUCUAAAACUGUGUUGCACUCAAGUUCAUUUCUGUGUAGCCCCUGUUACGUGGGGGUACAGGGCACAUAAAAUAGCAUUAGAAGAGUCUUUUCUAGACCAGCACGGUGGUACACACCUGUCAUCUUAGAACUUUGGGAGGCCAAGGUGGGAGGGUAGCUUGAGGCCAGGAGUUAAGACUAGCCUGGGCAACAUAGCGAGACCCUGUCUCUACAAAAAAUAAAAAAUUAGCCAGUUGUGGUGGCACAUACAUGUAGUCCCAGCUACUUGGGAGGCUGAGGUAGGAGGAUUCCUUGAGCCCAGGAAUUCGAGGCUGCAGUAAGCUGUGAUUGCACCACUGCAUUCCAUCCUGGUUGACAGAGCAAGACUGUCUCUUUAAAAAAAAAAAAUUCUUAAAGUGUUUGUUCUAAAAACUAAAAGAUGUUACAGGGAACUGGGAAAUCUUAAAUCCUCUGCCAGUAUUUACUUUUACUAGUGGUUAAUGAUCCCUACCUCUAACCUUUUUUAGAUAUUUUAAGAUUUUUUGUAGUGCAUAAGAUGAUUGCUUUCUUACAUUAGUUUGAAAUACUUUGAAUCUAAAUUAAUUUGAGUAUCAUUUGAAAAUAAGAUGUUUUCUUUUUUCAAAGUUUUAUAGCUAAAAUGACACUAGAGGGCAGCCUGUUACACAUGACAUUUAAGACUCCAUUGAGGAUUUCCCCUGCAAACACUUCUUACUAUUUCUGCUUUGGAUUAACUGAAAAAUUAAUUUCAUGCUAUCACUAAUAAAUACUUAUAUGUAUAAAAACAUGAAAUGCAGUUAAAAUUAUAUAACUGUUUCAGCAAUUUUAAAUGAUAGGAGUUUAAAUGAAACUUAAAUUUUCAUUUAAAUUUUAAAUGAAACGGAGUUCAGGCAAUUAUAAAUGCUUUGAGGAUAGGCCAGGUUACACAGAAUAUGAAAAUCCUGCCUAAUGUCUUAGUGCCUUAAGUAUGGUUUAUCAAAAUUGAGUAAUUUGUGCUUACAGUAAUAUAGGCUGCAAUUUUUGUUUCUUUGAGCAAUUUAGAAAAUAUCUCUUUGAGCAUUAUUUUUAAAGUCACGAAACUUGAAAUAUUUGAUAAGGUAAAAGUUACAUAAACAAAGCUAUUGUUAAUAUUAAGUCUAAGACCUUUCAAAUAUUUUGGAAUAUAAAAAUACUUUUUAGGUUUACCAAAUGAUUAUUUAGAAAUAGCCAGAUUUUGCCUUCUGAUAGCUUUUAUUCCUGUGUUUUCUACUUCCAUUAAAGAUUAUUCGAUUUGUCUUGCCUGUAGUGAUGUCAUGUUCCAUCCUUUUCAGCAAGCAAAAAGUGCUCUUUCCUUCAGUCUGACUUUAUUUUUUUCAAAGAAAUAAGAAGAAGUGAAAUAGACUGGCAAAGAAGUUGAUUGCAAUUUUUUAAAUAAUUUUUUUUUUUCACUCUCCUGUAUUUCAAUCUUCUUUCUGUAAAAACUUACUGUCUUCCUAGUCUCUUUGUUCUUUGAAAUUGUUUUCACAAAAGGGAGGAAACAGUCCAUUUGUCAAAUUAAUCACAAUGCUGACGUGAAAACAGUAACUCUUUGCAGACUCUAGAACUGUUUGGUUCAGUAUCACAUCAAUAAUGUAAAUUAUUGCCUUCUUUUUAUAUUUGAGAUCAGUGUUCUCACCUCAUCUGUUUGCAGAUUUACAUCUUGUACAGCAUUUGUGAGAAGCUUUUUAAAGCACAUAGACCCCCGUGUUCUCUGCUUCAUAACUUAAUAUUUGAACCUAUUUCUAGUUCUUCUGCAAACUUGCCAUGGUUUUUGACUUAAGUAAAAUAAAGACCCUGUCCCUUCACUAAGGCUGAGGACAAGGGUGGUUCUACAGUGCCUUAAGUAAACCCAGCCUUCAUCAUGAUGGCUCAUCCAGCAGGGUGUUUUGCUGGCUUUGACCCUGUUGUUUAAGUACUGUUCAUUAUGAGAUGUUGGCAGGGUAAUUAUCUGCAGUCAUAUUUGUGUGUGGUGUUUGCCAAGGAUGCACUCCCUCCCUAAAAGUUAAUGUCUGUCCUCAGUGAUCUCAAGAAUACUUCACUGAAAUAGUUUCUGAUGAAUUAACAACCUUGAAAAAUCUUUGCCCACAAAUAUUUUGUUGUAGACUUAAAAAAAAAAUUAGAAAAUGCAUCUAAAUUCUUUAAAAGCAGAUUCACUUAUGUAUAUCUUCCCUCUUUCCCAGAUAAGAGUAGUGUCAUUUUAGAAAUCAUUUGAGAAACUUCUUGAACGAGGAUAAUCUUUUUAAUGAUUCAUGACAUAUAAAACAGAACUAAGUUUUGAUUUAUUAUAUGAAGUGUCUAUUCCUUGGAAGAAUGAUAGAAUUUUUUGUUUUUCAGAAAAGCAGACUGCUCUAUAUUAUGUUAGAGACCGAAGGGAGGAGCACUUUCACUUCCUUUAUAGAAUGGAAUGUGGUGGCACAGGGACUCCUUGUGGGACAGACGUUUGCUUCAGCCUGCCCAGGUGUGUGACAUUUUGAAGGGUGUCAUUUUGGUAAUCUGCUAUUUUAUGAUGCACUAUGUUGACUACUCCAUGAUGUACCACCUGAUAAGGGGGCAGUCCGUCAUCAAGCUCUACAUCAUCUACAACAUGCUGGAGGUAGCUGAUCGUCUGUUUUCAUCUUUUGGACAAGACAUAUUAGAUGCUCUCUAUUGGACAGCAACAGAGCCUAAAGAAAGAAAAAGAGCCCACAUUGGGGUGAUUCCUCACUUUUUCAUGGCUGUUCUCUAUGUCUUUUUGCAUGCAAUUCUUAUAAUGGUUCAAGCAACAACUCUCAAUGUAGCUUUUAACUCACACAACAAGUCUUUGCUUACUAUCAUGAUGUCUAAUAAUUUUGUUGAAAUUAAAGGAAGUGUUUUCAAGAAGUUUGAAAAGAACAAUCUCUUUCAAAUGUCAAAUAGCGAUAUUAAGGAACGAUUCACAAAUUAUGUGCUUUUACUGAUAGUGUGUCUAAGAAACAUGGAACAGUUUUCUUGGAAUCCAGAUCAUCUCUGGGUGUUGUUUCCAGAUGUCUGUAUGGUAAUUGCAUCAGAAAUUGCCGUGGAUAUUGUAAAACAUGCCUUUAUUACUAAAUUCAAUGACAUUACUGCAGAUGUCUACAGUGAAUAUAGAGCCAGUCUUGCUUUUGACCUUGUUAGCAGCCGACAGAAAAAUGCAUACACUGAUUACAGUGACUCUGUAGCACGGAGGAUGGGCUUUAUUCCUCUCCCACUAGCUGUUUUACUCAUCAGAGUUGUAACAAGCUCAAUUAAAGUGCAAGGAAUCCUGUCUUAUGCCUGUGUCAUACUCUUCUAUUUUGGGUUGAUAUCCCUGAAAGUACUUAAUAGCAUCGUGCUGUUGGGGAAAUCGUGCCAGUAUGUGAAGGAAGCCAAAAUGGAAGAGAAGCUGUCGAAUCCUCCCGCAACCUGCACUCCAGGCAAGCCGUCCAGUAAAUCACAGAACAAAUGUAAACCCUCUCAAGGCCUUUCCACAGAAGAAAACCUGUCUGCCUCCAUCACCAAACAACCUAUUCAUCAAAAGGAAAAUAUCAUACCAUUACUUGUGACAAGCAAUUCUGAUCAGUUUUUGACAACUCCAGAUGGUGACGAGAAGGACAUAACGCAGGACAAUUCUGAAUUAAAACACAGAUCCUCAAAGAAAGAUUUGUUAGAGAUAGACAGGUUCACAAUUUGUGGAAACCGAAUUGACUGAAUCUGUGGCUUCAUGCGCUGAAGAAGCUGGGUCCUGGGGCAACAAGUGCUGUGUUGCCAGGACAAAUAGAUGCUAAACAUGGCACUUAAAUAUUUAUUUAAAAACUUAAAUUAUUAUUGGCAAGCAAAUCUUAGUAUCUUUCUUCCAGUAAUAUGGCCUGGCUGAGGGUCAGACCACAGGACAGGAGCGACCUCCGGCCUUGACUGUCUGGGAAGCUUGAUGGAUUAUAAAACUUCCUCCUGCCUGGCCAAGCAGCAGCAUCAUUUCCAGGACCCAACAAAGGCAACAUCAAAAUCUGUUUUGCUUUGUCAGUCUGGGCUUCCAGAAUGUUGAAUUUGCCUCAAGGCCUCUUCAGUAUAAGGAAAUACCUGGAAAACUGUGAAACUUUUACCACGACGUAAUCUUUCCAGUCUCAUACUAUUUUCACAAACAGUUUUCAAACGUUACUUCAUCUGCCAAAGCAUUAAAAAAAUUAAACAUAAGUCAAGAUAAAUGUUCUUACCACCAGAAUAACCCUUAAAGAUGUAUCUUAAUUAAUCAGAAUAAAAGGCUACCUUAAAUAAGACAUGAUGAAUAGUAGCAUUUUGUAGGGUUAAAAAAAAAUGCUAAACUAGUUUAUUUAUUAAAAAAAUAAUUAAUGAAGGCUAUGCAUUACUGGGAAAAAUCCUUCAUAAUUUUUCAGUUUACUCUUUAAAGCAAAAUGUGAGCUGUAUGUCAUUUAAUUGGUGGAUAAAACAAAUUUCCUUACAAAAGGGCACUUUUUACACCAAGGAAGCAGAGCAGUGUUAACUUUAAGGUAUACUUAACUGAUUUUGCUUUAAAACUAAUUACUUCAUAAAUUAUUACAGCUAAAAGGAUUCGAUGUUGAACAGGCUGAAAAAUUGUCAAUGUACAAAAUUCAAAACUGUCAACUUUAACUGUAAAGUAAAUGCUCCAAGUGUGUUAGACAGCAUCAUCUUGCUUGGGCUUACCAAAUGCAUUAGUCUUUGUGUUUGGGUCGACAGCGAGUGUGCCUGUGCUGGGGCAGGGUGUGUGUUCUGUGGGAGGGUGUCUGUGGGGAUGUGACUAUCAGGGUGGGCCUGUGCUGGGGAUGGGGCAGGCCUGGGUCUGGAGAGGAUUUUGUGUGAAAGUAAAUGGGGUGUUUGAGGCGUAUGGGUGGCUGUUGGUGUGGGGAGGCAUCUGUGUAUGGCUGUUGGGAACAGCAACCAAAAGGUGCUUUUUGGUUUUAUUUGAGAUGAAGAUUGUGUUUCCGCUUAAUUACUAGUUUGUGGUCUAUAUCAUAGAAGUUAUUUCCCACCCCAUUUUAUCUUGACAACCGUGUUUGCAUUUCUGUAAAACUUCUACAACUUCUGGUGUCAGAACUGUCCAGAAGAUGGUACUGUUAACUGUUAUUUCCUUUGAUGUUUUGAUUUUGAAGUUUAGCUCUCAUGCAAAUGUUUCAGGCGUACAUACAUAGGCAGAAAGCAAUUUUUAGGUGAUUUGUCUGUUUCUUGGAUGAAAUAUAAAGCAAGCUUUAAUGUUCUGACUUGUUCAUUUGAAAUACAAAAAAGUAAGUGAAUUUUAAUGUUUUGCAUUAACUAAAGAAAUCUGAAGAUUAAUGUUGAGGAAAUUGUAUGGACAUGCCUUUGUGAAACCAGGAAGUAUUUUAAGUUAAAAAUGAAAAAGGUUUUAAUUGCUUUGUGUGUGUUUUAAUGGAGCCCCAUUUUAGAAUUAUUUUUUCCAUCUCCCUUUACCAACAAAAGGAACAAUGCCACCGUGAAUGGAAUAGUUUGGGGAAAGCUUUGCCAAACACAACCCUGAUUUCAGAGCAGGAACAUGGUUUGGAUAGAUCUUCAGUUCCGCUUGAAUUAUUCUGUUACUGCGCUGUCAUUUUCAGAAGAUUUCCAUUCCUUUGCAGAUGCUGUUGGGAGUUCGGGAUUAUGUUCAUUUCUUCUGUUUUAAUGGCAUUCAGUACUAAUUUUAUAAGUGCAUCUUGUGUGAAUCUCAAUAAAUUCAGUUUUGUAAUCUUUUUUAAAAAGGUCACUGAAUUUAUUUUAAUAUUUACUAUUGUAUUUGGUAGAGUGAAUUUCCCACUGUAUAAUAAGUAUUUAUUUGUAAUUCACAAGUGAUAGAGCUAUCUUAAUUUGAAUUAUUGCUUUGGUCUUAAUGGUGGCAAAAUGUUUAAUUUUGUCUUUGGAAAAAAUAGGCUCGGCCUUGAUUAUAGACCAUUUAAUAUUUCUCAGCAAAUGAAGGUAUUUGCAUUUUACAAGUGUUUUGAAUGUCACACAAAAUAUUUUUCACAUCUGGGAGUCAAGUUCAAGACAGUGCUUUGGUUUUAAAAAAAUCUAAUGAAGGCACAGGAUAGGCCAGACCCUUAUUAGGUUUUCCUUUAGAAUAAGUGUAAAGACCAAGUGUCACUGAUACGCUUGUCCAGAUUUUCUUGUGGACUUUGGCCAGUAUUUAGAGUUUAUAUUCAUGUUACAUAAAGUGAAAGAAACUUGCUAUAAUUAGGCCAUCAAAAUAUAUCCUGCCACUCCUGGUAACUCAGCAGAGGAGGAGAUAAAUUUACAAAAUAAUGUAAUAUCUCUACAUUGUUACAUGUUUUCAACUAUUUUUUAUCAACAAAGAUUUGUUAAUCACUUCCUAUGUGUCAGAAACUGUUCUAAGUGGUGGGAUCAGCAAUGAGCAAGAUAAGUCCCUGUUCGUCUGUGGAAGACUGAUAGGAACAAGUCGAUGAAAUAAUGUCUGCUGGUCACAGAGUGUCCACUGACCAAAUGAUCUCUCAGGCUUAUUUCAGCUCUAAAAUAUAGUUCUUUAAAACGUU